GCAUUGUGCAGCAGGCGGGCCCCCGCGCGGUAGGGCCCUGGACCCGCGCGGCUCCCGGGGAUGGUGAGCAAGGCGCUGCUGCGCCUCGUGUCUGCCGUCAACCGCAGGAGGAUGAAGCUGCUGCUGGGCAUCGCCUUGCUGGCCUACGUCGCCUGUGAGUGCGCGCCCGCUGCCAGCUGGGGAGCCCCAUUCAUUCCCCGGCGCCGCGGUGGGCCGGGCGGCGGUGGUUCGGGGCCCCGAGGCGGCCCUGCAGCCCCGCGUUGCUCCCCGCCCCGGGCGGGGCCGGCGCUUUCUGCUCCCACCCCUUUCCACUCUUGCAGCAAAGCGGGCCAACUUGGGCGCACACCCCCUACCGCUUAGGCCCGGGCGCGGACCCCGGGCGGAGGGGCCCCUAGCAGUCCUCGGGCGGCCCCAGGUCUCUGCCUCCUGCCCGGGCGCGGGGGACUCGGCGGCGGCGCUGUCGUCCAUGUCGCGCUGGGAGCCGGCGAGGGUCCCGGUCGGGGACUCCGGAGCGUGCCGCGUGGGGAUACCCUUGGGGACAGCCGAGGUCGCGCCGCGGUGUCGGUUAAGUCGGAUAAAAAUACUGUGGCCAUUGGCAGAGCCCCCGCUCCGACUGUUUGCUCCUCAGGAAAAUUACUCAGCGUUUAACUCUUGGGGAGCCAAGUGUGGGCGGCUCCCCGGCCCGCGGCCGUGCCCAGGUGUCGGGGCGCACCGGCAUCCCCAUUCUAGGUUUUCCCCCGGGGCUCGGCGGCCGGGCGAAGCAGGCAGGCAGCUGGGUGGCCGGGCAGGGCGUGCCUGCAGCUUCUCUGUGCGCGGGUCCAGUUUCUGUCAUCGCUCACAGCAUGCUGCCUGGAGACAGGGCAGGAGGGGCACUUCGCAGGCAGGUGGUCGGCCCUCUGCUUGUUAGGGAAGUCAGAAACCGUCCUUUUAAAGAUCUAUUCGUUGGGAAUGUUUUAAUUGAUGCUAUUAAUACGUUACCAAGUAGCAAAAUUGGACUAGAAAUAGCUCCCAGUGUGAGCUGCGUUUGAAUGCUAGCCACCCAGACACACACUGAAAUGAAAUCACCUGCUAACCUGUUGGCGUUACCAAGAUCUGAUUCCAGAGCUGUUUGGGGCAACUUCGUUAAUAUGAGCUUUCUACUCAACAGGUCUAUCCAGGAAAAUGGUGAACUAAAAAUUGAAAGCAAGAUUGAAGAGAUGGUUGAACCACUAAGAGAGAAAAUCAGAGAUUUAGAAAAAAGCUUUACCCAGAAAUACCCACCAGUAAAGUUUUUAUCAGAAAAGGAUCGGAAAAGAAUUUUGAUAACAGGAGGCGCAGGGUUCGUGGGCUCCCAUCUAACUGACAAACUCAUGAUGGACGGCCACGAGGUGACCGUGGUGGACAAUUUCUUCACGGGCAGGAAGAGAAACGUGGAGCACUGGAUCGGACAUGAGAACUUCGAGUUGAUUAACCACGACGUGGUGGAGCCCCUCUACAUCGAGGUUGACCAGAUAUACCAUCUGGCAUCUCCAGCCUCCCCUCCAAACUACAUGUAUAAUCCUAUCAAGACAUUAAAGACCAAUACGAUUGGGACAUUAAACAUGUUGGGGCUGGCAAAACGAGUCGGUGCCCGUCUGCUCCUGGCCUCCACAUCGGAGGUGUAUGGAGAUCCUGAAGUCCACCCUCAAAGUGAGGAUUACUGGGGCCACGUGAAUCCAAUAGGACCUCGGGCCUGCUACGAUGAAGGCAAACGUGUUGCAGAGACCAUGUGCUAUGCCUACAUGAAGCAGGAAGGCGUGGAAGUGCGAGUGGCCAGAAUCUUCAACACCUUUGGGCCACGCAUGCACAUGAACGAUGGGCGAGUAGUCAGCAACUUCAUCCUGCAGGCGCUCCAGGGGGAGCCACUCACGGUAUACGGAUCCGGGUCUCAGACAAGGGCGUUCCAGUACGUCAGCGAUCUAGUGAAUGGCCUCGUGGCUCUCAUGAACAGCAACGUCAGCAGCCCGGUCAACCUGGGGAACCCAGAAGAACACACAAUCCUAGAAUUUGCUCAGUUAAUUAAAAACCUUGUUGGUAGCGGAAGUGAAAUUCAGUUUCUCUCCGAAGCCCAGGAUGACCCACAGAAAAGAAAACCAGACAUCAAAAAAGCAAAGCUGAUGCUGGGGUGGGAGCCCGUGGUCCCGCUGGAGGAAGGUUUAAACAAAGCAAUUCACUACUUCCGUAAAGAACUCGAGUACCAGGCAAAUAAUCAGUACAUCCCCAAACCAAAGCCUGCCAGAAUAAAGAAAGGACGGACUCGCCACAGCUGAACUCCUCACUUUUAGGACACAAGACUACCAUUGUACACUUGAUGGGAUGUAUUUUUGGCUUUUUUUUGUUGUCGUUUAAAGAAAGACUUUAACAGGUGUCAUGAAGAACAAACUGGAAUUUCAUUCUGAAGCUUGCUUUAAUGAAAUGGAUGUGCCUAAAAGCUCCCCUCAAAAAACUGCAGAUUUUGCCUUGCACUUUUUGAAUCUCUCUUUUUAUGUAAAAUAGCGUAGAUGCAUCUCUGCGUAUUUUCAAGUUUUUUUAUCUUGCUGUGAGAGCAUAUGUUGUGACUGUCGUUGACAGUUUUAUUUACUGGUUUCUUUGUGAAGCUGAAAAGGAACAUUAAGCGGGACAAAAAAUGCCGAUUUUAUUUAUGAAAGUGGGUACUUAAUAAAUGAGUCGUUAUACUAUGCAUAAAGAAAAAUCCUAGCAGUAUUGUCAGGUGGUGGUGCGCCGGCAUUGAUUUUAGGGCAGAUAAAAGAAUUCUGUGUGAGAGCUUUAUGUUUCUCUUUUAAUUCAGAGUUUUUCCAAGGUCUACUUUUGAGUUGCAAACUUGACUUUGAAAUAUUCCUGUUGGUCAUGAUCAAGGAUAUUUGAAAUCACUACUGUGUUUUGCUGCGUAUCUGGGGCGGGGGCAGGUUGGGGGGCACAAAGUUAACAUAUUCUUGGUUAACCAUGGUUAAAUAUGCUAUUUUAAUAAAUUAUUGAAACUCACCA